CCGCCCGCCCAGCGGUCCGGUCCAGGCGCCCGCGCAGAAUCAGCUGUCUGAGCUGCCCAGGCGGCGGGGGAGCAGCGAGCGGGCUUCAGCGAGCCGCAGGAGGCACAGGCCUGUCCUGGGUCCCCGCAGGUCUGCGCGUCUGUUGUUCCCAGCGCUCUUGGAGGCCUGCAAAGGAAGAGCAACCUGUCCAGACUCCCCGCAGGACAGGAAAAAGAGAAAUCUCGACAUGGAAAAACCCUACAAUAAAAAUGAAGGAAACCUGGAAAACGAGGGAAAGCCAGAAGAUGAAGUAGAGCCUGAUGAUGAAGGAAAGUCAGACGAGGAAGAAAAGCCAGACGCGGAGGGGAAGACAGAAUGCGAGGGAAAGCGAAAGGCUGAGGGAGAGCCAGGUGAUGAGGGACAACUGGAAGAUAAGGGAAGCCAGGAAAAGCAGGGCAAGUCCGAAGGUGAGGGCAAGCCACAAGGCGAGGGCAAGCCAGCCUCCCAGGCAAAGCCAGAGGGCCAGCCGCGGGCCGCCGAAAAGCGCCCGGCUGGAGAUUAUGUGCCCCGGAAAGCAAAAAGAAAAACAGACAGGGGGACGGACGAUUCCCCCAAGGACUCUCAGGAGGACUUACAGGAAAGGCAUCUGAGCAGUGAGGAGAUGAUGAGAGAAUGUGGAGAUGUGUCAAGGGCUCAGGAGGAGCUAAGGAAAAAACAGAAAAUGGGUGGUUUUCAUUGGAUGCAAAGAGAUGUACAGGAUCCAUUCGCCCCAAGGGGACAACGGGGUGUCAGGGGAGUGAGGGGUGGAGGUAGGGGCCAAAGAGGCUUACACGAUAUCCCAUACCUUUAAUGCCUUUGGCCUUCCAUUCUGACUUCUCUGAUGAGAUUAUUGUCAACCCUGCUUUCCCUGGUAGAUAUUUGCCAGGCCCAAUGCUUUAACCUUAAGCUGAUAUUUUUGCUUUAGAUGUCAAUCUCGUUACCAGCAGCCUUUUGACCCAACUACAGCGCUCUAUAUUUUAGUAGAGGAUUUUCACCCAUGUGCAUGGAAAAGAUGUUCAUGACACAUUGUAAAAAAUAAAUAAAUAAAGAACAGUUUGCAGAACCUCGUAUACGGUUAUCAGCCAAUAUUUAUAAAAAUGUAAAUGUUUGUAUAAUGCAUUUCUGCGCAAAGAAAACCCUGAAAGCAUGUACACUAAAAAGCAGGCAAUGGUUAUUCCUGAAGGGUAGCCAAGAAUAGGUCUCACCUGUAUUCAAAAAUGAGUCCUACCACCUCUUGUAUGUACCUCCAUGAUAUUCCUCUGCUGCUGUGCACAUCCCUAUGUCUUCCCUAGGUCGAGCCAGGUCAGUGGGCACUGUUGCUAGGUCCUCUAUCAUGUUCCUGGGUCUUCUAACAUGAGUGCUGGGUCUGCAUACUCAGACCCAUACUAAAAUAUAAUACUAAAUAUUUGUCAUACUGAAAAAUAAAUAAAAGCUGAAUACAAUACAUACUAAGAAAUUGAACUGUUUGGUGCGCUUACAAAGGCAAUAAAGACACUCAGAAUUCCUGUUAUCAGAACAUAAGAUGACAGGUAAAAUUCAUAUUAUCUCUGGGACUAAAAGCUAAAGGAAUCAACCUGGAAAUUCUAACAGAUCUAUUGCUGUAAGAGUCAAUCUUGUCAUUUGUAAAAUAAGGGUAAUACUUGCCUCACAGGACUGCCUGGUGGAUCAGAUGAGAUACUAAGUAUGUGAGCUGUGUUGUGACCUGGUCCCCACUAGGCACUCAGGGGAGGAAUGGCUCCUAAACUAUUCCCAUACAGUGGCAGGAAAGUCGAUGGAAUCAGACACAUUGGAGGAGGACUGAGGGAGUUCUCACCAUGUCUAGGAAUAUUUCCAGGCAGCUAAGAAGUAGAUGCCACUCUCUCCUGGAUACUUCCAUGUCUGCUGGGCACUAUGCCCUUUUUCCCGGGUCCUGCACCCUUUACUGAUAGAGGAUUUAUGGUGUCAAAGCCCUGUCAUUUUCUCUGGAGUCACUGGUGAGCAAUGUCCACCAACCCAUGACCCCCGUAGAAGUGGAUAAAGCCCUCUCUCCACUUUAUAGUUACAGUAACCAGGUACACAUGGAUAUCACCUUGGUGCUGCUUGGGCCUCUCAUUAAUAUCUUCCAAAUUCUUUUUGCCAAAAUAAUCAUUUAUGUGUAUUCCUUAUUUCUUUGUUUUGCAUACAUAAAUAUUGUCCUCACAAAACUGAGAUAUUGCAGGCUAGGCCAGGAAAAAAUACCUGCAUGAUAGUGGUUGUGCUGUUCUCAUGGGUUAAUAUCUUGUCUGCAGAUGCUCUUUUCUCUGUUGAGUUCACUCUCAGGAAACUUGUCAGGUAACACUUUAGCAGUUCGGCAGACCCAUCAAUACAUUUGAGUUUUAAAUCCUUUGUAAUGAACAUGUUGUGGUCCAUGAAAAAGCUGCAUAGUCAUCACCUGGGGAACUAAUUAGAAACGCAGAAUCUCAGGUCUUGCCUCAGACCUAAUAAGUUAGAAUCUUCAUUUUAACAAGAUCCCAAGAAGAUUCCUAUGCACAUUGAAGUUUGAGAAGCACUGGCUUAGAAAGAGACCCUUCAGGCUCCCCACUCCCACCUUUACAUAAAAUAUGUGCCUAAAAAUAUAAAUAUAUGUGCUAUAUAAGACACACAUCACAGAUUAUUAAAUAAGCCCAUGUUUUUCAAAAUGAAGUUGUCCUUCCCCCAUGAAAAGUAGAUCUUGAAAUCAAUUCAAUGGGUCAAGAUAGGUAAUUUUUUAAAAAUGAAAUAGGAUAGAAUAGACUUGAAUACAGCCAAACAGAAAAUAUCAAAUAGCAAAUAGCAUUGUAAAUAGACUGAAUAUUUUUUGUGAAAUUUGUGUUUCAGUUACGUACGUAUGUAUGUGUGUGCACCAUGAGUUAUGAUGAAAAUAAAUUUCUGACUGUGGGCUGCAGCAAAAAAAUUGAGAAAGACUGCACUGGAUUCUGCAUCUCAAAGUAUGGCAUGUCCAUUUUAUAUUUGUAUUGCUAGUGCCCAACACAAGUAACUGACAAGUAGUAAGCACUUAAUAAAAAUGUAAAUAAUAAUGAC